UGAACAAUUGCAUGUACUACCUUAGUUCUGUAAGGUUUCUCUCUAAAUAUUCAGAUCAUCGUGUUUGGGGAAGAUACUGUGUAAGUUUGCUGCUGCAAGAAGGAAAGCAAACACCACUUGACCCUCAACGUUUUCUCCCAUGAUUUUUCCUCCUAUGAAUUCUUGGAUGACUUCUCAGAACUCAGCUCUUUUUAUUCAACACAGGCUCAUUCUGCAAUACUCCACCUGAUACAUAGCUAUGGAGCAGAGCAAUUAUUCCGUGUAUGCCGACUUUAUCCUUCUGGGUUUGUUCAGCAACGCCCGUUUCCCCUGGCUUCUCUUUGCCCUCAUUCUCCUGGUCUUUUUGACCUCCAUAGCCAGCAACGUGGUCAAGAUCAUUCUCAUCCACAUAGACUCCCGCCUCCACACCCCCAUGUACUUCCUGCUCAGCCAGCUCUCCCUCAGGGACAUCCUGUAUAUUUCCACCAUUGUGCCCAAAAUGCUGGUCGACCAGGUGAUGAGCCAGAGAGCCAUUUCCUUUGCUGGAUGCACUGCCCAACACUUCCUCUACUUGACCUUAGCAGGGGCUGAGUUCUUCCUCCUAGGACUCAUGUCCUAUGAUCGCUACGUAGCCAUCUGCAACCCUCUGCACUAUCCUGUCCUCAUGAGCCGCAAGAUCUGCUGGUUGAUUGUGGCGGCAGCCUGGCUGGGAGGGUCUAUCGAUGGUUUCUUGCUCACCCCCGUCACCAUGCAGUUCCCCUUCUGUGCCUCUCGGGAGAUCAACCACUUCUUCUGCGAGGUGCCUGCCCUUCUGAAGCUCUCCUGCACGGACACAUCAGCCUACGAGACAGCCAUGUAUGUCUGCUGUAUUAUGAUGCUCCUCAUCCCUUUCUCUGUCAUCUCGGGCUCUUACACAAGAAUUCUCAUUACUGUUUAUAGGAUGAGCGAGGCAGAGGGGAGGGGAAAGGCUGUGGCCACCUGCUCCUCACACAUGGUGGUUGUCAGCCUCUUCUAUGGGGCUGCCAUGUACACAUACGUGCUGCCUCAUUCUUACCACACCCCUGAGCAGGACAAAGCUGUAUCUGCCUUCUACACCAUCCUUACUCCCAUGCUCAAUCCACUCAUUUACAGCCUUAGGAACAAGGAUGUCACAGGGGCCCUACAGAAGGUUGUGGGGAGGUGUGUGUCCUCAGGAAAGGUAACCACUUUCUAAAGAAAUUUCAUAUGCUGCUAGAGACUUGAAAUGAAGGAUACAAGACUUUAUCAUUGCCCUUGAAUUUAAAUAUUCUCUGCCUGGAAACAAGUG